CUAGUCUCCCAGCUCCAGCUCGGCCUUUGGGUUUGCUGUGGUGUCCUUGUCUCCUGCAGGACCGGCCGCAGCAUGGACGCUCCCAGGCGGUUUCCGACGCUCGUGCAACUGAUGCAGCCAAAAGCAAUGCCAGUGGAGGUGCUCGGUCACCUCCCUAAGCGGUUCUCCUGGUUCCACUCUGAGUUCCUGAAGAAUCCGAAGGUAGUUCGCCUUGAGGUUUGGCUGGUGGAAAAGAUCUUCGGCCGGGGCGGAGAACGCAUCCCGCACGUCCAGGGUAUGUCCCAAAUCUUGAUUCACGUGAAUCGAUUGGACCCUAACGGCGAGGCUGAGAUCUUGGUAUUUGGGAGGCCUUCUUACCAGGAGGACACAAUCAAGAUGAUCAUGAACCUGGCUGACUAUCACCGCCAGCUCCAGGCGAAAGGCUCAGGAAAGGCCCUCGCCCAGGAUGUCGCCACUCAGAAGGCCGAGACCCAGCGGUCUUCAAUAGAAGUCCGGGAGGCCGGGACGCAGCGUUCGGUGGAGGUCCGGGAGGCCGGGACCCAGCGUUCGGUGGAAGUCCAGGAGGUCGGGACACAGGGUUCUCCGGUGGAGGUGCAGGAGGCCGGGACCCAGCAGUCUCUCCAGGCUGCCAACAAGUCGGGGACCCAGCGAUCCCCCGAAGCUGCCAGCAAGGCAGUGACCCAGCGGUUUCGCGAGGAUGCCCGGGACCCAGUUACUAGAUUAUGAAGGCAUCUCAGGCCCUGGAGCCAGAGCCAGUCAGGGGUUAAAGUGAAAGCCCGUAUUUCCGCCCAGAAGCUGGGGUUGGGGAGAGGAUGUGGAUUUUUUGUUUUACCCUUUCUGUUGCAUGGUUGCAAACACAAACUUGAGUUCUAAUAAAGAAUUGCAAAGUGGAAGCCCGCCCCCCGCCUCCCCCCCGCCUCACUUAAGUCCAGGAAGCUGGGGUGGCGAGGAAGGAUGAUGUGGAUUGUUUUUGUUUUACACCUUCUGUUGAAUGGUUGCCAACACAAACUUGAGUUCUAAUAAAUAAUUGCAUUUCC